CUGCAGCCUGCCUGGAAGCUGAAGGAAAGGUGGGGGCAUUGUAGGACACCUUGAACCCAGGUCUCCCAACUUCACAGGACUCCCUUCCUCCGCCCAGGAGUUUUAAGGAAGAGGAACUUCCUGGUGGGACAUAUUGAGUGCCAAACGUGUGUUCACAUAAAAAAUCAAGAGAUCAGGGCAUGAGUCUGCAUCUGAAAACUCGAGUAAAAAAUCCGGUGUAUGCUGUUAAUGGAAAGAACAGAAUAUGACACUUGCAUGCCGCAUAUUCUCACUUCGUUCCUUGGGGGUGUGCUGCUACCUCUGGUCACUGGCAUCGGACUUUUCUUCCUUCUUUCUACUUUCCUACAUCUCCCAAGUUUUGUAUUUUGAGCAUGUGUUAGCAUUAUAACUGCUAAACAGGAAAGAUGGCCUUUAAAAAGAAAGUGAAGUGUAAAAGUUUGAGGGUGAUGAAAUAAAUGUGCUUGAGGAAGAAAAAGCAAUCUCAGUUUAAUCCUAUGGUUGCCCCAGGAGGCACUAAUUUAUCCCUUCUGCUUUUCAAGUGAGGAAGCUGCAGCUUGGCGUAGUUCUGGGGGGAGUAUGAAGCUGCCUUGGUUUAGGUGAUGGAGCACAGGUCCACAGACAUGUGUGGGUGCAUCUGUGGCAGGGGAGAAAAGAGCAUGUGUCCAGACUACAGCUUGUUCAGAGCUGGGACACUGACAAUAGAGCACGCACUGCGUGCGUAGGUGGGUGUGUCUCCGAUCCUCCAGCAGUGACAGGGACGAAGCCUUGCCCUGUGGGAUGACUCAGGCCACUGGCCAAAUGUUAUGUCUCCAUGUUCAAGUCCCUCUCCAACUUCUCCUCCUGGGACAGAAACAGAUGGCAGCGGAGCAGGAGAAGGUGGGGGCAGAGUUCCAGGCACUGAGGGCUUUCCUGGUGGAGCAGGAGGGUCGGCUGCUAGGCCGCCUGGAGGAACUGUCCCGGGAGGUGGCACAGAAGCAGAAUGAGAACCUGGCCCAGCUCGGGGUUGAGAUCACCCAGCUGUCCAAGCUCAGCAGCCAGAUCCAGGAGACAGCUCAAAAGCCUGACCUUGACUUUCUCCAGGAAUUCAAAAGCACGCUGAGCAGGUGUAGCAAUGUGCCUGGCCCCAAGCCAACCACAGUCUCUUCUGAGAUGAAGAAUAAAGUCUGGAAUGUUUCUCUCAAGACCUUUGUCUUAAAAGGGAUGCUGAAGAAGUUCAAAGAGGACCUUCGGGGAGAGCUGGAGAAAGAGGAGAAAGUGGAGCUCACCUUGGAUCCCGACACGGCCAACCCGCGCCUCAUCCUCUCUCUGGAUCUUAAGGGCGUGCGCCUCGGCGAGCGGGCCCAGGACCUGCCCAACCACCCCUGCCGCUUCGACACCAACACCCGCGUCCUGGCGUCCUGCGGCUUCUCCUCGGGCCGGCAUCACUGGGAGGUGGAGGUGGGCUCUAAGGACGGCUGGGCCUUUGGCGUGGCCCGCGAGAGCGUGCGCCGAAAGGGCCUGACGCCCUUCACUCCCGAGGAGGGCGUCUGGGCCCUGCAGCUCAACGGCGGCCAGUACUGGGCCGUGACCAGCCCCGAGCGGUCGCCCCUCAGCUGCGGGCACCUGUCGCGCGUGCGGGUGGCCCUGGACCUGGAGGUGGGAGCCGUGUCCUUCUACGCUGUGGAGGACAUGCGCCACCUCUACACCUUCCGCGUCAACUUCCAGGAGCGCGUGUUCCCGCUUUUCUCUGUUUGCUCCACGGGCACCUACUUGCGAAUCUGGCCUUGAGGGGCACUGCUGGGGAGCUCCUGUCUCUGGGCUGCCGGUGGGAGGGGAUGUCGCCUCCCCAGAGAUGCCUGGUCCGUCUUGGGUCUGCCCUCCGUGCUCCUGACCCCUGCUGCCCAAGAGAGCCUGCUACAGACACAACCCCGAGGCAGGAGAGUGACUGUGGCCAACCGAGCAGGGGAACAGGGGCUUUGGACUCCUGAGGGUGUUCCCUUCCUGAGGUCACAUGUGGAUUUGGCCAGAGCCUUCAGGAGGUGGAGGCCGGUGAGGUCAGGAGCCCAGCUCUCCAGGGGGCUUCUGCCCUGACUGGGAAGGGUGCCUGGCUCCCUAAAACAAUGUCAAAGCCAGUCCUGCUGUUCUCUGUUGCCAGGGGGCAGGUCUGGGCCUGGGCCAACCACGUUUGUUAUCAUGGCUGCUGCCUUCUGGACAGCUGCCAGCUCUGCCUUGAGAGGUUGUGGGACCUCUGGAUCCAGCUGACCUGACAGGUCAUCUACUCAGGGAGGAGCCCUGUGCUCCCAGCUCAGAGGACAGUCUGGGCCAGAACUGGAAGGAGACAUCUGUCCCGUCUUUGAGUGACAAGCCCGGGACAACAGCCAGUGGGCAUCACGGCUCUCCAGCACUCCUUAGCCGGAGGAUACAGAGUGAUGGGUGCAUCCUGACCAAUGCGACAACCAACACGUGCUCUCACAAACCCCUGACUCCCGCACUUUCCAGUGCCAAAGUACAAACGCUGCUUGGAUAAGGAGAGCAAAGCUUCUGGAACUUUAUUUACUCUUUCUUUUUAAUUUUCUUUUAAGAGACUGGGUCUUGCUAUGUUGCCCAGGCUGGUCUUGAACUCCUGGCCUCAAGUGAUCCUCCAGUUUCCAUCUCCCUAAGAGCUGGGAUUACAGGUGUGAGCCGCUGUACCCGAACUUUUUUUGUUUUUGCUUCUGGAACUUUGAAACACAAAACACAAGUUGGCACUUACAAUUUUAAAGAUGCAGCCAGCUCUAAACAACACACAGAGCACAAAUAUGCUCCUGACGGACUCAGGAAAAUGCCAACAGCAGAGCACCCUGGUGCCAAGGCCUUCUCAGCCCAUGCCCUGGAGGGCAUUCCCCUGGCCAGCCUCAGCCCCUUGUCUACUUGUUCUCCAGCUUCUGGGUAGCUGGGCUUCUGGAAGGGUGGCAGUGGGCUACUCCCUGCUCAGCGCUCCCCUGGGAAGGGGGUGAGGAGAUGAAAAUGAAACUAUGAGCUGUCUUUGGA